AGAGGUGCACCACGUGGGGUUUGCUGCCGGAGCGGAGUCUCCGGCCGGCGUCCAGUUUGAGUCUAGGUUGGAGUUGGAACCGUGGAGAUGCGGAAGGAAACCCCACCCCCCCUAGUGCCCCCGGCGGCCCGGGAGUGGAAUCUUCCCCCAAAUGCGCCCGCCUGCAUGGAACGGCAGUUGGAGGCUGCGCGGUACCGGUCCGAUGGGGCGCUUCUCCUCGGGGCCUCCAGCCUGAGUGGGCGCUGCUGGGCCGGCUCCCUCUGGCUUUUUAAGGACCCCUGUGCCGCCCCCAACGAAGGCUUCUGCUCCGCCGGAGUCCAAACGGAGGCUGGAGUGGCUGACCUCACUUGGGUUGGGGAGAGAGGUAUUCUAGUGGCCUCCGAUUCAGGUGCUGUUGAAUUGUGGGAACUAGAUGAGAAUGAGACACUUAUUGUCAGCAAGUUCUGCAAGUAUGAGCAUGAUGACAUUGUGUCUACAGUCAGUGUCUUGAGCUCUGGCACACAAGCUGUCAGUGGUAGCAAAGACAUCUGCAUCAAGGUUUGGGACCUUGCUCAGCAGGUGGUACUGAGUUCAUACCGAGCUCAUGCUGCUCAGGUCACUUGUGUUGCUGCCUCUCCUCACAAGGACUCUGUGUUUCUUUCAUGCAGCGAGGACAAUAGAAUUUUACUCUGGGAUACCCGCUGUCCCAAGCCAGCAUCACAGAUUGGCUGCAGUGCGCCUGGCUACCUUCCUACCUCGCUGGCUUGGCAUCCUCAGCAAAGUGAAGUCUUUGUCUUUGGUGAUGAGAAUGGGACAGUCUCCCUUGUGGACACCAAGAGUACAAGCUGUGUCCUGAGCUCAGCUGUACACUCCCAGUGUGUCACUGGGCUGGUGUUCUCCCCACACAGGCUGGACCUUUCACAACCCUCUCCUCCAUCUGAUAGUGUUCCCUUCCUGGCCUCUCUCAGUGAAGACUGCUCACUUGCUGUGCUGGACUCAAGCCUUUCUGAGUUGUUUAGAAGCCAAGCCCACAGAGACUUUGUGAGAGAUGCGACUUGGUCCCCGCUCAAUCACUCCCUGCUUACCACAGUGGGCUGGGACCAUCAGGUCGUCCACCACGUUGUGCCCACAGAACCUCUCCCAGCCCCUGGACCUGCAAGUGUUACUGAGUAGAUUGGAUUUAAGACAAAAAGCAAGUCCCCCAUGAGUGUCCACUUCUUUGCCCUGCCCUCUCAGCUUGUGAGACAACACAGGAGCCUUCUAUAGUAUGUUGAUAUGCUAGAUCUGUGCCGUUAAUAGGCAUCGUCUCUCAGCCUGAGGGAGGCUGGAUUCUGGGUUCCUGUAGUCACAGGGAGGAAAAGCUUUCUUAAAAAUGGACAUGUAUGUGCGUGUGAGUGUGUGUGUAGAUUUAUAGUUUUUGGUAGUGGCAGGAAUAAAAAAAAUCCAUCCUACAUCUUCCCUAAGCACUGCCUCUCUCUCACCCCCCAAAACAAGUUGACGAAAGGGUUUUAUGUAGCUGUCUAUGAGGAAUUGGCCGUGUCUGGGUGGGUUAUGGGAUGUGGGCAUCCCUGGGUUCUUGGAAGCAGCUCUUAUGCUACUCAUAGAGAUGGGAUUGACUUUAUUUUUUUAUAGUGCUUAAUUCACCAUUAUGAGAAAUGCUUCCAGUCACAAAAAUGCAGCCCAGCUCACUCUGAGGAAGAAGCAGGACUUGGUACGGUUUUACACAACUCCUUACCAUUAAACUGAAUCAGAAAUCCAUUUUCUGGCUGAAUAAAAAGUUUGGCUUGCCUGUGUAAUGCCCACUCCCUUCCCCCUGGCUCCCUAGUGAUGGGACAUAUAUGAGAGAGAAGUGUUUUUCUAUCAUAGACACCAUAGGGGAAAGUUUGGGGAUGAAGGAGAGCUUAAAGGUGUUUCAAUUAAGUUAGAAAACUGACACAGGCUGUUGAGAAUUCUUUGCCACUUUUCCCACCCCAAAACAGCAUGGGGCCUGACAUCUUCUGCCCUGGUCCCCUUUCUCUUGAUGUGGAAAGUCUGAAUGCAGUAUUUAUAGACUUCUAAGGUUUUAAAAUCCAGUAUCAAGAAGAAAAUCAGAAAUACUGGUUGGUGAAAUAAAGAGUUUAGGCAUUGUUGGCCUGUCUUUUUUGAAGCAUGUGUGUUAUGUGUAGUUAGAUAUAUUUCACUUAUGUGAGUCAUCAUGGUGUUGGUCUUGUAGCCCAUUAUUUUUCCUGUGCUUCCCCAGCUUCCCAAAGUAGCUAGUUAGAACUUAAGGUAAAUAUUUAUUCUUGGGUUGGUGGAGUGGAUAUUGCCAGUUAGGAGUCAUGGAUCAAUUACUGAUUAUAUUGAAAGUAAAUAUAAUCAAUUAUGUACUUUUGAGCUUUGCAGGUUCAAUUUAGGUAAAAAUCACAUUAUGAAACUGGGAAAGUCUGAAGGAAUAUGGGCAAAAUAUUUCUCAGUAAAGCUUCCAUGCUUCACCCUUGACAUGAUUACCCUUGAGUAAAACAUGGGAAUUUGUA